GCAGUUAACUCCGCCCUGACCCACCCUUCCCGAUGCAGUCCCUGAUGCAGGCUCCCCUCCUGAUCGCCCUGGGCUUGCUUCUCGCGGCCCCUGCGCAAGCCCACCUGAAAAAGCCAUCCCAGCUCAGUAGCUUUUCCUGGGAUAACUGUGAUGAAGGGAAGGACCCUGCGGUGAUCAGAAGCCUGACUCUGGAGCCUGACCCCAUCAUCGUUCCUGGAAAUGUGACCCUCAGUGUCAUGGGCAGCACCAGUGUCCCCCUGAGUUCUCCUCUGAAGGUGGAUUUAGUUUUGGAGAAGGAGGUGGCUGGCCUCUGGAUCAAGAUCCCAUGCACAGACUACAUUGGCAGCUGUACCUUUGAACACUUCUGUGAUGUGCUUGACAUGUUAAUUCCUACUGGGGAGCCCUGCCCAGAGCCCCUGCGUACCUAUGGGCUUCCUUGCCACUGUCCCUUCAAAGAAGGAACCUACUCACUGCCCAAGAGCGAAUUCGUUGUGCCUGACCUGGAGCUGCCCAGUUGGCUCACCACCGGGAACUACCGCAUAGAGAGCGUCCUGAGCAGCAGUGGGAAGCGUCUGGGCUGCAUCAAGAUCGCUGCCUCUCUAAAGGGCAUAUAACAUGGCAUCUGCCACAGCAGAAUGGAGCGGUGUGAGGAAGGUCCCUUUUCCUCUGUUUUGUGUUUGCCAAGGCCAAACUCCCACUCUCUGCCCCCCUUUAAUCCCCUUUCUACAGUGAGUCCACUACCCUCACUGAAAAUCAUUUUGUACCACUUACAUUUUAGGCUGGGGCAAGCAGCCCUGACCUAAGGGAGAAUGAGUUGGACAGUUCUUGAUAGCCCAGGGCAUCUGCUGGGCUGACCACGUUACUCAUCCCCGUUAACAUUCUCUCUAAAGAGCCUCGUUCAUUUCCAAAGCAGUUAAGGAAUGGGAACCAGAGUGUUUUAGGACCUGAAGAAUCUUUAUGACUCUCUCUCUUUCACUCUUUUUUUUUUUUGUCACUAAGUUAAAAGCGAAGUGAGAGUAUUAACGUUUUUGUUCUCCUCCGGCCCCCUGUUACAAUGAAGGGGCAAAAGUAUUUGCUCUUAGUCUAUUCCUCCCUUAACUUCUGUGACUAAUUUUUAUUUCCUUUCUAGAUUUGCCCAAUUAAUACUAGGGUGCAGUGUAUCCUGGAGAGGUAGGGUGUGUGGGGGAGGAAUCCCUUGGGGGAGAUAUUAGGAGUGCUCUGUUGUUUACAAACUCAGGUACCCGCAGGGCCUAGCAAGAGACUUAAAUGACUGAUAAGAACCGUGAGAAACAUGUUGCUUCCAGGCUUGAUUUCGAUUUUUCGCUUUUUUUUUUUUUGAGACAGAAUCUCACUUUGUCACCAGGCUGGAGUGCAGUGGUGCAAUCUCACCUCACUGCAACCUCCGCCUCCUGGGUUCAAGCAAUUCUCCUGCCUCAGCCUCCCAAGUAGCUUGGACUACAGGCCCUGCCACCACGCCCGGCUAAUUUGUGUAUUUUUAGUAGAGAUGGGGUUUCACCAUGUUGGCCAGGAUGGUCUCGAUCUCUUGACCUCGUGAUCUGUCCACCUUGGCCUUGCAAAGCGCUGGAUUACAGGCAUGAGCCACUACACCCAGCCGAUUUUUCCUUUUUGAUUAAAGAUGCUAUUACAAUGUAAAUAUUUCUUACACAGAAAGUCACAGCACAUGUGCCCAUUGAUACAAGGCUGCUGAGGCCUGGUCUCCAGUUGGAAAUAUAAUUAAGGGUGGCAAGGACUGGAGUCAGUUGGAGAGUGCAUAGCCAGUCUGUGAAGACAACUGCCAGAUACUGGCAAUACUCCAGCCUGGUGACAGAGUGAGACUCUGUCUCAAAAAAAAAGUUUCAAUGUUUACUCCUAGAGAAGCCAAAAAUCCAGAUUUGUAUAUGAAAUCUUACCAUUUUAAAAGAUUGGCAGCUAAUUAUUUUUUUAAAAAGCUGUGCAGUGUGAUGUGUCCCAAACGGACUGGCUCAUGGGUGGCCACGUCACAACCUCUGAUCUCAGACCGUGCAUGCCUUGUCCUCUUAAGACAACUCCUGUGGCACCGUUUCUCCCUCCACAGGGCCAAAGCCAUAGUGUCCGGUCCCAAGGACAAGGCUCUUCCAGUGCUAGGAGAGGUAUGAGCAGCCUCUCACCUGUGAGCUGUGGGGAUCACAAGGCUGCCUGCCUCAGUCUUGGAGUCCUGUUGGGUGAAUGAGGCAGAUGGGAAAGAGCCUCACCAGCAGCUGCUUUUGGAGCAGGGGUCCAAGGAAGAGAGGGUGGCCUCGACAUCAAACUGCCUGGAUUUUUCUACCACCCUGUUACAUCAUAACAACUUCUGAAACACACACCAGCCCUGAGUUCUGGGCUCAUUUGAAGCCUGGAAUAGCAAUAAAUCUUUUUAACUUGCGGACAGUUUCCCCUUGCCUUGGCUGCAUAUUUCACUGAUCACAUCUCAGGAUUUCAAAAGCAUUUUUGGGGUGGGGCUCUUUUGGUUGGAAGGGUUUGUUGGAACGGUACAGGUGAGCCGAGGUGAUUCCAGGGACGGACCCUUCUGCAGGAGCUUGAGCUUGCUUGUUGUCUCUGCUUCAUCGCCAUCCAGCUCCCUUGUUUGCUAUUUUGCUUUCCAUCACAUCAUGACUGCGGAGAGCAAAAAUCACCUAGUGACCAUUGAACAGGUCCCAGAGACAAAAUCUUUUUAUCUGAGGAAUUUAAAAGGGAGCAAAGACCACCUGGUGACUAUCAGGCCAUGCAGAGGCAAAACGCCUUAUUUGGGGAAAAUUAAAAGUAAUUAGACUUUCCUAUUAUCUAAAGCAGGCAUCUGGUUCCAGAUUUCUUUUCCCCGAAAAAAACCUUAGAAGUAACUAAAAUUUCUGUACAUCUCCGGAAUGCCAUGCUGAAACUCACUGCAACCCCACGGUCCCGCUUUAAGGUCCAUAAAUAUCCCUAAGGAAAAAUCCACCGUGGUACAUUCAGUCCUCUCACCGAGGUGCCCCAUGGCAGUCUUCUGCAGCAUUCUUCUAAUACCUUUCCUUUUUCAAACCUAUACUGUUGUUGGUGAAUUCUUUUUACCAACCCACGAGUUGACCACUUCCCAAUGCCGGGGAUCUGACACCUCACCUGGCAAUGACCUCCACAGCCGUUUCCCUCUGUUGGAUCUUCCAGCCUUAUUCUCAACAGUUCAUUUUUAGUUCACAUUCUUGACCGAAUCUCAGUAGCUCAGUUAAUCUUUUUAUGUCUGCUCUGCUCUUGGGUCAUAUGUUCCGUGAGGUUUCUUAGGGGUGGGGGAUGAGGAGUUAAAGGUGGCAUCUUCAAUCGCAGGUCAAAGCAGACUUUAAUAAAUGGUGCUGAGCCAACUGGAAAGCCCCUUGGAGAAAGUUGAAGUUAGACCUGUACUUCACACCAUAUGCAAGAAUGAACUCCAUCUGGAUCCAGGAUCCAAAUGUAAGAAAAUGAAGCCAUAUAAAUACAGAAGGAAACGUGGUGGAAAUAUCCAGUGGCAACAAAAUAUUGACACAUUUGACUACAUGAAGAUAAUAAAAAUGCUUAGUAAAAACACAAUAAAAUCAAAUGACUGGGAGAAAAAUUUAUCCAGCCUAUAUAAUAGACAAA